AGACUCGAGAUGCGCCCGAAGAGGUUGGGCCGGUGCUGCGCGGGGAGCCGGCUCGGACCCGGGGACCCAGCAGCACUCACCUGUGCACCUUCGCCCUCAGCCAGUCCCGCUCCGGAGCCCUCUGCGCAGCCGCAGGCACGGGGCACUGGACAGAGAGUAGGAUCCCGAGCCACCUCUGGAUCCCAGUUCCUCUCGGAAGCCCGCACCGGAGCUCGCCCGGCCUCGGAGGCUGGAGCCAAGGCAGGAGCCCGGCGCCCGUCCGCAUUCUCGGCCAUCCAAGGGGAUGUCCGGUCUAUGCCCGACAAUUCGGACGCGCCGUGGACCCGCUUCGUAUUCCAAGGGCCGUUUGGUUCCCGGGCCACUGGCCGGGGGACUGGAAAGGCAGCGGGCAUCUGGAAGACGCCAGCCGCCUACGUUGGCCGGCGACCCGGGGUGUCCGGCCCUGAGCGCGCCGCCUUUAUUCGGGAGCUGGAGGAAGCACUGUGUCCUAACCUACCUCCGCCAGUCAAAAAGAUCACCCAGGAAGACGUCAAAGUGAUGUUAUAUUUGCUGGAGGAGCUUCUCCCACCUGUCUGGGAGAGCGUUACCUAUGGGAUGGUCCUGCAGAGAGAGAGGGACCUGAACACUGCAGCUCGCAUCGGCCAGUCCCUGGUGAAACAGAACAGUGUUUUGAUGGAGGAGAACAGCAAGCUGGAAGCCCUGCUGGGCUCAGCCAAGGAGGAGAUUUUAUACCUCAGACACCAGGUGAACUUGCGGGAUGAGCUCCUCCAGCUCUACUCAGAUUCUGAUGAGGAGGAUGAGGAUGAAGAAGAGGAGGAGGAAGAAAAGGAGGCAGAAGAGGAACAGGAAGAAGAAGAAGCAGAGGAAGACCUGCAGUGUGCUCAUCCCUGUGAUGCCCCUAAGCUGAUUUCGCAGGAGGCAUUGCUGCACCAGCACCACUGCCCACAGCUGGAAGCCUUGCAGGAGAAGCUGAGGCUGCUGGAGGAGGAGAAUCAUCAGCUGAGAGAAGAGGCCUCUCAACUCGACACUCUUGAGGAUGAGGAACAGAUGCUCAUUCUGGAGUGUGUGGAGCAGUUUUCGGAGGCCAGCCAACAGAUGGCUGAGCUGUCGGAGGUGCUGGUGCUCAGGCUGGAAAACUAUGAACGGCAGCAGCAGGAGGUCGCUCGGCUGCAGGCCCAGGUGCUGAAGCUGCAGCAGCGCUGCCGGAUGUAUGGGGCUGAGACUGAAAAGUUGCAGAAGCAGCUGGCUUCGGAGAAGGAAAUCCAGAUGCAGCUCCAGGAAGAGGAGACUCUUCCUGGUUUCCAGGAGACGCUGGCUGAGGAGCUCAGAACGUCUCUAAGGAGGAUGAUCUCAGACCCUGUGUAUUUUAUGGAGAGGAAUUAUGAGAUGCCCAGAGGGGACACAUCCAGCCUAAGGUAUGAUUUUCGCUACAGUGAGGAUCGAGAGCAGGUGCGGGGGUUUGAGGCUGAGGAAGGGUUGAUGCUGGCAGCGGAUAUCAUGCGGGGGGAAGAUUUCACGCCUGCGGAGGAGUUCGUGCCCCAGGAGGAGCUGGGGGCUGCCAAGAAGGUGCCGGCUGAGGAAGGGGUGAUGGAAGAGGCAGAGCUGGUGUCAGAGGAGACCGAGGGCUGGGAGGAGGUGGAACUGGAGCUGGAUGAGGCAACGCGGAUGAACGUGGUGACAUCAGCCCUGGAGGCCAGCGGCUUGGGCCCUUCACACCUGGACAUGAAUUAUGUCCUCCAGCAGCUGGCCAACUGGCAAGAUGCCCAUUACAGGCGGCAGCUGAGGUGGAAGAUGCUCCAGAAAGGUGAGUGCCCCCACGGGGCCCUCCCUGCCGCCAGCCGGACAAGCUGCAGAUCGUCGUGCCGAUGAAAAGAGAGGGUGGAUAAGCUCCCCGAGUGCUCACCUGCCCCAGCCUGGCUCUACCUGCUGUGCUUAUUUGCAUGGACUUUGCAUAUCAUUUGCAUAGACACCUCUGAUCCCCUUCAGUGGGAACCGUAGUGUCAGUGCUCAUUUAUGUGGCAUUUGCUUAGGAUUCCAGAUCUCCAUCCACUUUUCUCCUGGGGGCUGGGCUGGGGGUUAGGGCUGGGACUGUGCCCCCACACUGCGCCUCAGCUUCCCAUCUCUGCCCGCUUGCUUCCCCUGCCCCCAACCCCUGCCUCCUCUAUCCCCCAGGCUCUCCAACUCUGCAGCAGUGGCAGCAGCAGUCAAAACAAACACGGGGGGCGGUGGGUGGGAUGGUGGAGCAGCCCGGGGGCUGACCCAGGCUGGAGGACAGGGCCAGCCACCCUCCCACGGCCUGGGAGGAAGAGAGGCCUUCUGGGACUGCCCAGGCUAUGGGGACAAAGGCCUUCACCAGCAAGGGCCACAGUUGGAACAGUCCCCUGGGUGUCAGAAGGUGGGCUAGGGCCUCCUGCAGGGUUGUGGGGUGGAACAGGGUCUCCUCUCCCCAGCCAGAAACCCCAAAGUCUGGGAGCUGCACCUUCCGAGUGCAGGCCAUGUGAGCCCUGCCUCUUUAAGGAGCCGCAGGACAUGAAAGAUGACCUUGUGACACUCAUGCACAGCAGCCAUUGCACGUGCAUCAGCUCCCAUCAGCCUCAUUCCGUGGCAGGUGAUGUGUCCCCAUUGGUUAGGUGAGGAGGGUGAGGCUCAGAGAGCUAAGGACACUUGUUUGGGGCCACACAGCCGGGGUAGAUCUGAGCCCGUCCUCUCUACUCCUGUGCUGUAGCACCUUCACUGGCCCAUCCCUCCCCUCUAGUGCUGUCCUGGUACCCGUCCCAGCCUGUCCCCAUUCUCAUGGCCCUUUGGUCACUGCCGGGUGGAAUAGCACUGGCUUCAGCAGGCGUGUCAUGUAAGCUUGUGCAGGUUAUAAACUGAACCAUGACCUUUAUGGCGCAUGCAGGGGGCAACCUGCAUAAUUAUCAAUGGCGACUUUCCGUGUCCUUCUGAUACAGUUGAUCAGACCCCUGCCCACCGCCCAGGCCAGGCCUGUGGUCAUCAAUGCCCCAGUUCACAUCCACCUGCUUCUCUUCCAGGCUUUGCUGUUCCCCAGCAGCCUGCAGAGGCCCCACAGACAGCUUGAGGCCCCUCCUUCUGCUGCCUGGCCAAGCCCCACACCCGCAGACCCUCCUUCCCAUCCUCUGAAAUGGGACCCUGUGUCUGUCACCAGCCCACCCUCUGUGUUCAUGAACCUGGGCUGGAGCUUGGGGACCCCUCCCUGCCCCUGGCUUCCUCUUCCAUGUUCUGCCCUUUCCCACAUGUUGGAGGCUUUUCCAACGUCUUCAGGGACAGGCGGUAGGAACCCCGGCCCUCGCUCUGCAGCUGGUGCAAAAGCUGUGGCUGCCAGGUCUGGGCCACAUGGCAGCCCAGGGGGCAGGAGAAGCCCGGGAGAGGCCCACUGGCUACCAGACUCAGCCCUGAGCAGGGAACAGGGCCCAGCUUCCACCGGCAGGGAGUUGUGAGCGCCUUCCCAACAAUGUGCCCCUCACCCCUUGAUGCCCAUGCUAAUGGUAGCCACCCUGGUUCUUGUUGACUUGAGGGACCUGGCUGUCUUCCCUGUUCUUCAUCCUUUCUUCUCAGUCCCUACCUACUGUUUGUAACCACAAGUGUCUCUGUGUGUGGGUGGGUGAGGGCCCCUCUGCCCAGUGGUGUGUCUCCUCUCCCUCCCUCCCUCUUCUGCCAGUGGCCUGGGGGUGUCCAGGCUCCCAUCCGUGGCCCAGCCCCUCUCCCCUCUGUCUUGAUCCCCCCCUCCCUGCCCCUGGCUUCCUCUUCCAUGUUCUGCCCUUUCCCACACCUUUGUUCCUCAAUAGCUGGGGGCUGGGACUGAGGCCUCCUGCAGGUACCUGCCCCCCUUCACACAGCACCUCUCAAUCUCCUAUUGCUUGUCAGCCUGUGUGCGUGUGGUGCAGGAAAUAAAGGAUCUAUACCCUCCUG